GUAUGCGUCACGGGCGUCAUGACCUCGCUGUGGCCCCGGCAGCGGCUGCGGGGAAAGUCGCGAGGUGCAUCCGCUUCGGCUGCAGCUAUUUACUGAGGACCCACUGGAUGUCAAGCAUUGUGCAUAGUUUUCUUCGAUUGUUGCAACAUCCCUUGCGAGAGUUUCACUCCUGUUGCCCAGGCUGGAGUGCAAUGGCAUGAUCUCAGCUCACCGCAACCUCCGCCUCCUGAGUUCAAGCAGUUCUCCUGCCUCAGCCUCCUGAAUAGCUCGGAUUACAGUUUCUGGAGCAGCAGAGCUGAAGGAACCCAAACUUGGACUGAAGUGACUCUACUAAGGUCAGCUCUAUGGCUCUUCCACAUGAUUCAAACGAAACUUCCUAUUUGCUGCCUCCCAACAAUGAGGACUGGGGCAGGCAAACCAUUCCUGACUUUGUUUAUGGGCAGAAGGAUCUCAUGGCAGAAGGGAUUCAGUGGCCAAGGAAUGCACCUGGCAUCCCAGAUGCUCUGCCACAAUCUCCCUUUGAUGCUGCACUCUGCUCUGCCUGGAAGCAGCGGGUGGAGCUGGGGCUGUUUCGCUACCGUCUACGGGAGCUACAGACCCAAAUCCUCCCUGGUGCUGUGGGUUUCGUGGCUCAGCUGAAUGUGGAGCGUGGUGUGCAGAGGAGGCCCCCGCAGACCAUCAAGAGUGUGAGGCAGGCAUUUGACCCUGUACAGUUCAACUUCAACAAGAUCCGGCCCGGAGAAGUCCUCUUCCGUUUGCACCGGGAGCCUGAUCUCCCUGGGACUCUGCUGCAAGAAGACAUCCUGGUGGUGAUCAACGUCAGCCCCCUGGAGUGGGGCCACGUGCUGCUGGUGCCUGAGCCUGCCCGCCAGCUCCCCCAGCGCCUGCUGCCGGGUGCACUGAGGGCAGGGAUUGAGGCUGUGCUGCUGAGCUUACACCCGGGCUUCCGUGUCGGCUUCAACAGCCUGGGAGGCUUGGCCUCGGUGAACCACCUCCACCUGCAUGGCUAUUACCUGGCCCACAGACUGCCCGUGGAGCAGGCGCCAAGCGAGCCCCUGGACCCUGGAGGCCAUUUGCAUCUGCUCCAGGACCUCCCAGCUCCUGGCUUCCUCUUUUACACUCGUGGGCCAGGGCCUGACUUGGAGUCCUUGAUAAGCAGGGUAUGUCGGGCCACUGAUUAUCUGACUGACCAUGAGAUUGCUCAUAACUUGUUUGUCACCCGGGGAGCUCCGCCGGGAAAGACAUCACCUUCCUCAGCCCUCACAGGGGUCCGAGUAAUUCUGUGGGCCCGGAAGUCCAGCUUUGGGAUAAAGGACGGUGAAGCUUUCAAUGUUGCCCUCUGUGAGCUGGCUGGGCACCUCCCUGUCAAAACAUCCCAGGACUUCAGCAGCCUGACAGAGGCAGCUGCUGUGGCCCUCAUUCAGGACUGUCGGCUGCCCCCAUCCCAGGCAGAAGACGUACAGGCAGCACUGGUGGCCCUGAUGUCCCAGGAAGAGCAAUAAUACUUCUGGAUGUAUUUAUGUUCUUUUUUUCUUUUCUUUUGAGAUAGGGUCUCACUCUGUCCCCAGGCUAGAGUGUAGUGGUAUGAUCCUGGCUCACUGUAGCCUCCACCUCUGGGGCUGAAGUGAUCCUCCCACCUCAGCCUCUUGAGUAGCUGAGACUAUAGGCGUGCACCACCACACACCUGGCUUUUUUUUUUUUUUUUUUUUUUUUUAACGAUUAGGUGAUUUUGUAUUUUUUUAUAUAGACAGCGUUUCACCAUGUUGCCCAGGCUGGUCUUGAACUCUUGGGCUGAAGCAGUCCUCCCACCUCGGCCUCCCAAAGUACUGAGAUGACAGGAGUGAGCCCCUGGAUUCUUUUCUGUUUCUUUUUUUUUUUUUUUUUUUUUUUUUUUUUUUGAGAUAGUCUCGCUCUGUCACCUAGGUUGGGGUGCACUGGUACAAUCUCGGCUCACUGCAACCUCCACCUCUAGGGUUCGAGUGAUCCUCCUGGCUCAGCCUCCCGAGUAGCUGGGACUAUACAGGCUCCUGCCACCAAACCCGGCUAAUUUUUUUGUAUUUUUAAAAGAGAAGGGGUUUCACCACAUUGGCUAGGCUGGUCUUGAACUCCUGACUUUAGGUGAUCCGCCCGCCUCGGCCUCCCAAAGUGCUGGGAUUACAGGCGUGAGCCACCACACCCAGCCAGGAUGUAUUCAUUUUCUACCUGAUGAGUCCCUUUCCAGAGCACUGUCCAUCAUAGUCCUUUGGACAUUUAUUUUCAUGGCUGCCUUCUCACCUGUCUCAGCCUAAGAAGAAGGAUGAAGAAAGCUGAUAAUGAUCUCUUAAAGGGGAGAAAGAUAAUGGUCUCUUUAAAGGGGAGCUGAUAGUGGUCUCUUUAAAGGGGAGAAAAUCUGGAAUAAUUCUACUGAGUAAGACAUCAUGAAUGUAUCUGCUACCUCUCCCCGUUCUUGUUCAAGCCCCAGGGGUGUUAAAAAGGAGUGUGUGUGACAGUUACACACUCCUGACUUUACAUUUAGAUUUUGUCUUCCUUUGAUAUCAAAUGUUAGCACGGUAAUAGUGCCUGUGCCUCCAGUAUUGAGCUGCCACUUCUGUUCUCAGCCUGUUUAUUCCCCUUUGCUCACCACUUAUUUUUAUUGCUUUGUCCCUUCUUUCCAUUUAGCCCUGCUCCACCCAAAUGCCCCACUCCUUCACUUUCCCUGCCACCUUGAGCUUUCCUCUAGCCCCCAACACCAAGUUGAAUGCUCUUCACUGACAUCAUCUGAUGUAAAAACACAGUGUUGUCACAACUUUCCGGGUGCACGUCUUUUUUUGUUUUGUUUUUUUGUAAGGCUGGGGUGCAGUGGUGCAAUCACAGCUCACUGCAGACCCAAACUCUUGGUCUCAAGCCACCCUCCCACCUCAGCCCCCUGAGUAGCUGGGACGAUAGGUGUGCACCAUCACACCUGGCUAAUUUUUAAAUUUUUUGUAGAGAUAGGGUCUUGCUAUGUUGCCCGGGUUGCUGUCAAACUCCUGGCCUUAAGAAAUCCUCCCACCUCGGCCUCCCAGAGUGCUAAGAUGCCACCACACCUUGGUGCAGGUUUUUUUUUUUUUUUUUUUUUUUUUUUUUUGACACAGGGUCACUGUCACCCAGGCUGGAGUGCAGUGGUAUGAAGACAGCUAACUGCAAGCUUCAACCUCCUGGGCUCAAACAAUACUCCCAUCUCAGCCUCCCUAGUAGCUGGGACCACAGGCAUGCGCCACCACACCCGGCUAUUUUUUUGGAGAGAUAGCAUCUUGCCAAGUUGCCCAGGCUGGUCUCGAACUCCUGGCCUCAAGAUCCUCCCACCUCAGCCUCCCAAAGUGCUGAGAUUAUAGGCAUGAGCCACUGCACCUGGCCUGAGUUUUUUUUUUUUUUUCUUGAAUCAGAGUUUCACUCUGUUGCCCAGGCUGGAGUGCAGUGGUGUGAUCUCGGCUCACUGCGUCUCUGCCUCCUGGGUUCAAGCAAUUCAGCCUGAGUCUUCUUAAUACCCCCAUUCAAAACGGGAUGGAGACUGACAGUUUGUACUUUGUUCAAGGUCAGGCAGCUGGAGUCGGGACUGCAGCACAGGCAGGUACCAGAAGAUGAGCUGGGACAAUGUGUGCUUGUGACCGCCUCUCCAGUCAGUGGUUCCCAUGGUGGGUAGCACUGUCCUUAACAGUUUGCCCUCCCUGAGCCUCAGCCAUCCCUCUUGGGGUCUUUCCCAAGCACUUUAGAAGCUCCUCUUGAUGUAGACACAAAAUCCAAAGCUAAGUCGUUGUUCCUCCGUCUGCAUCUGAGUCAAUGUGGGAAAUUUUUUUUUAUCUCAUUGCUUUGUUCUGUCCUGUUUCUCCAGACAUUUCACACUGGUUCCAGAGGAACUAGUCAGUAGACACUAUUCUAAGAGAGUAUGUGGGUGUGAAAUCUCAUUUUCCUUUUAGCUCCCUUGAAUGUUAUACAGCAAAAGUAAAAGAAGUCUUGGGUUGGCUGGGCACGUUGGCUCACACCUUUAAUCCUAGCACUUUGGGAAGCCGAGGCAGGCAAAUCACUUGUCAGGAGUUCGAGACCAGCCUGGCCAACAUGGUGAAACCCCAUCUCUACUAAAAAUACAAAAAUUAGGCGUUGUGGCGGCCACCUGUAAUCCCAUCUACUUGGGAGGCUGAGGCAGGAGAAUCACUUGAACCCAGGAGGCGGAGGUUGCAGUGAGCUGAGAUUGCACGACUGUACUCCAGCCUGGGCGAUAGUGCGAGACUCAGUCUCAAAAUAAAUAAAUACAUAAAGUCUUGGGUCCAGCUCUCAACAGAGAUUAUCACCGCCACCACUCCUUCAUCAAACAUCCUGAAGGAAUGAGAGUCCCUGUUCACAGCGUAAGGGUGAAAGGGGGCUCACACAGGUGGGUUCUGGCUGCUGUCUGAGUGGGCUCACCCAGGAGGGGUUUUGAUUUCUCUGCCUCCCAAACUGUGGGUCCUAGCCCUGGCUUAGGCCUUCAGGUCGUUGGCUCCCUAUACCUAGGCCUGUAUAAAGCCUUAGUUUCCAGUUUUCAUUAGAGGUUUUACAUCCCAAAUGAUGUUACAAAGUCUCCCUGUGAUAAAGCAGAAUAUGUGUCCAUAGCCCAUUUUAUAAGAAAAACAGUUUAGGCCAGGUGCGGUGGCUCACGCCUGUAAUCCCAGCACUUUGGGAGGCUGAAGCAGGCAGAUCACAAGGUCAGGAGUUCAAGACCAGCCUGGCCAACAUGGUGAAACCCCGUCUCUACUAAAAACACAAAAAUUAGCUGGGUGUGGGUGCACAUCUAUAGUCCCAGCUACUCAGGAGGCUGAGGCAGGAGAAUCGCUUGGACCUGGGAGGCGGAGGUGGCAGUGAGCCGAGAUCGCGCCACUGCACUCCAGCCUGGGCGGCAGAGAGAGACUUUGUCUCAAAAAAAAAAAAAAAGAAAAAAACAGUUUACCAUUCUAUCAGAAAAUGUUGACCACCCUCAUAUUUUUGGUAAACUGCAGUAAUUUUUCCUUAAUACUUUUUGCAAGCUUUUGCAUGCAUAAGCUCCAGUAUCACACUUAAUUUUGCUUGCUUGCUCUCUGAAGGGAGUUCGGAUGACCAUUACAGCAAAGUGGAUUUUGCGUUCAAAGUGAUAAGCCAAAUAUCAGGAUUUUCCCAGUUUCUCCGUAGGACUGAUGUUUAGAGGAAAGCCUUCCCUGACUCAAAUAUGUUUCUCCAUAUAAAAAGGGGAAAGUAAAAUGGGUUUUCUUUCUGGUGGUA